GCCGCGGUUUGUCGCCAGAAGGAAGAUGGCGGAUCUGGAGGAGCAGUUGUCUGAUGAAGAGAAGGUGCGUAUAGCAGCAAAAUUCAUCAUUCAUGCCCCUCCUGGAGAAUUUAAUGAGGUUUUCAAUGAUGUUCGGUUACUGCUUAAUAAUGACAAUCUUCUCAGGGAAGGAGCAGCCCAUGCAUUUGCACAGUAUAACUUGGACCAGUUUACUCCAGUAAAAAUUGAAGGUUAUGAAGAUCAGGUAUUGAUAACAGAACAUGGCGACUUGGGAAAUGGAAAGUUUUUGGAUCCAAAGAACAGAAUCUGUUUUAAAUUUGAUCACUUAAGGAAGGAGGCAACUGAUCCAAGACCCUGUGAAGUAGAAAAUGCAGUUGAAUCAUGGAGAACUUCAGUAGAAACUGCUCUGAGAGCUUACGUAAAAGAACAUUACCCGAAUGGAGUCUGCACUGUGUAUGGCAAAAAAAUAGAUGGACAGCAAACCAUUAUUGCAUGCAUAGAAAGCCAUCAGUUCCAAGCAAAAAAUUUUUGGAAUGGUCGUUGGAGGUCAGAAUGGAAGUUUACAAUCACUCCUUCAACCACUCAAGUGGUUGGCAUCUUGAAAAUUCAGGUUCAUUAUUAUGAAGAUGGUAAUGUUCAGCUAGUGAGUCAUAAAGAUAUACAAGAUUCCCUAACAGUGUCUAAUGAAGUGCAAACAGCAAAAGAAUUUAUAAAGAUUGUAGAAGCUGCAGAAAAUGAAUACCAGACUGCCAUCAGUGAGAAUUAUCAGACAAUGUCGGACACUACUUUCAAAGCCUUACGUCGACAGUUGCCAGUUACACGCACUAAGAUUGAUUGGAACAAGAUCCUUAGCUACAAGAUUGGCAAAGAGAUGCAGAAUGCAUAAGAUGAACAUUGCAUGACCGGAUCAUUUUAGUGUCUUUGCGUUAAAAAAUCAUUGCAAAAGUAUUCUGAACUGUCAAGCUGCCCAGUCAGAUGGGCUGUUGCCAUUUAAAAUCACUGUAAUUAAUUAGUUUGAUUAGAGCACAAAGCUUAGCUAAUCAACCAUUAUUUUUCAUUUUGUUUGUUCUAAGAGGAUUGAAAAUCAGUUUAGUUUAAAUGUCUUUCUGUUAGGCCUUUCUUUCUUACAAUGAAGAGAUGAUUCUUCUAGUUUAUGGUUAAAAGUUUUUGAAGUGUCUCAAAAAUAUUUUACUAACUGUAACCCUAAAAUUGAUGUCUUUUGGUUUAUGAAAUCAGUAAUUUUUGAUAUUUCCCCAGUUCUUUUUAAUGGGGUCAAUAAUGGACAUUCUAGUUUAAGGUGGUUGAUGGAUUUAGCCAUAUAUGCUGCUAAAGAAAUUGUCUACCUUUUCUUCCUCACCUGUUCCAUUUAUGUAAAGUUGAGAUUAGAGGGAAAGCAUUUUCUAUAUCAAUUGUGUUUAAACCUUUCAAGAAGGUUAUUUAGCUAGCUUAGUGUUGAACUAAAUUUUUUUUAAACAAGGCAAGGUCUAAUGCUGUUUUGAGAUUCUGAAAUUAAUGAAAAUACUUAUUUCAGAAAUGCAUUUAAUGCUUUUUUUCUUGUGACAGUUACGCAAAUCAGCUUGAAUUCCAUAUGUCCCUGAGUUAUUUUUAUCAUAAAGCCACAAAUGUAUUAUAACAAGGCAAAUUGUAAUAUAUAUAAUCCUGAACUCAUGACCAUGUCUCGGUUUAUUUUUUUUUUCUUGGAUUGAAAAGUACUGAAAUUCAAUGUGACAUUAAAAUGCAAAUUUUCCUAUUUAUUUGAGUAGAAAAUCACUUACCAGUGAGCAUAUAUAUUUUAAAAUACUUUCUUUGGAUAUUGUAAUUCUUAACUGGUUGUAAAUUAGAAAAGCUGGGAUUACAUAUGGUGUGCGGUUACAGUCUAAAUUUUUUCAUCCUCCUAUGCAUCAUAAGCAUGUUUGUAAUAUUUUCAAAAAUAGUUCUACUGAUGCUACAGGAAUUUCAAGCCUGUGGUGAAUGUUAGUAUUUACCAUAGGGAGUGAAGUGGAGUUAUGGUUUCAUUCAAUAGAGUAUUGCUGAUUAUACUUGAGUGGAAUCCUUUCCUCACGUACUCCCACAGACGUCUGGGCCUGGAAAUUUUUUUUUUAUUUUAUUUUAUUGUUUUUUUUUUUAGAAAAACACCACUUUUAUUAUGUACAAUAAAAUAUUUCAUUAGCUUGAAUUGUAUAGAUUUUUAAAAAUUCAAUGAAAGCAUGUUGUUUAAUUUCUUUUUAAAAUCACUGUUGGGCUUUGAAAGCAUUGAGAAUAUAAUAUGAAAUUAUGACAUUUUGUCUAAAUCAUCUUUUCUUUAGUUUUAAAAUACAAGUUUUGGCACAUUGGGAUUCCUAAAGAAAAUGAAUUGGUAACAUUAAUUAUCUGUUCCUUUUUAAAAUAUAUAUAUUUGAAAGUUUGAUGAUGGUGAACUAAAUACUAGAUCUAAUUGACAAGCUUAGUUGUAUCAGUUAGGCCAUCAUGAGUUUCUAUCCCAUGAAAGUCAUCAAUUUCCUAUCUCUGUUCUAGUCUGGAAUGCAUUACUGAAAAUGUAUGCAACUGUUUUUAAGGUGAUUUGCUUGUGAGACGGAAGAUUUAUCAAAAAUAAUUUAGAACAGGCUGGGCGCGGUGGCUCACAUCUGUAAUCCCAGCACUUUGGGAGGCCGAGGCGGGUGGAUCACGGGGUCAGGAGAUUGAGACCACCCUGACUAACACAGUGAAACCCUGUCUCUACUAAAAAUACAAAAAAUUAGCCGGGUGUGGUGACAGGCGCUUGUAGUCCCAGCUACUCGGGAGGCUGAGGCAGGAGAAUGGCGUGAACCCGGGAGGCGGAGCUCGCAGUGAGCCGAGAUCGCGCCACUGCACUCCAGCCUGGGUGACAGAGCAAGACUCUGUCUCAAAAAAUAAUAAUAAUAAUAAUAAUAAUAUAAUUUAGAACAGUCUGAAAUAAUGAUGGCACAGAAUAGUCUUUUAUAGUAUAAGAAUGGCAUUUAUUAGGCAGGGCACAGUGGCUCACACCUGUAAUCCCAGCACUUUGGGAGGCCGAGGCGGGUGGAUCACGAGGUCAGGAGUUCGAGACCAGCCUGACCAACAUGCUGAAACCCCGUCUCUACUAAAAACAAAAAAAAAUUAGCCGGGGAUGGUGAUGCGCGCCUGUAAUCCCAACUACUCAGGAGGCUGAGACAGGAGAAUCAUUUGAACCCGGGAGGUGGAGGUUGCAGUGAGCAGAGAUCGAGCCACUGUACUCCAGCCUGGGUGACACAGGGAGCCUCUGUCUCAAAAUAAUAAUAAUAAUAAAAGAAUGGCAUUUAUUAAAGUGAAAGAAGAAUGGAAACCCAGAGUAUCCUAUAGCUCAGGGAUGUAAUUUUAGUAGGAGACAUUAUGGCUGCUUUGCUGAGUAGGCUGAAGUGUGGUGGCAAAGGCAUAAUCAGGGAGAACAGCUAGGAGACUACUGCAGUAAUCUAGUUGAGAGAGCAUGCUGGCUUGGACUGAGGUGGUUGCUGUAGAGGUGGUAUAAAGCAGUGAGGUCUAGGUAUAUCCUAAAGGUAAAAUCAGCAAGACCUGGGGAGAGUUUGGUCAUGGAGUGUGAGAUAAAGAGAACCAUGUCUGGGGCUGGAGAAAUUGAGGAAGAUUCUUGUAGGAGCAAGUUGGUUUGGAGAAGAAGGCUGGUCAGGAGCUCAGUUUUCUAUUCAAAGGAGAAAUAUCUCAUGUAGCAGUUAGAUACAGGAGACAGGAACUAGAGGAAAGCUCUGGGCUAGAAGAAUGGGAAAGUGCAUGAACCUGGAAACAAUUUUAUAGGCAGACAGGAUGAAGGACCUCAAGGUUAGUGAUAAUGAAUUUAAAGUAAAUGAGACCAAUGAUGAGCAUGGCUGUAUGUUUUUCUUCAACCGUGUAAAGCUGUUUGGGUGCAGGCAUAGAGUAGAUGAAAUAAAUUUCACCAGGGCUGUGGUUUUGCCCAGAGUGAAUGACCACAUGAAGAGGGGCAGGGUAUGAUGAUGGUCUGUGGAAUUUCAGCUGGGUAAGCAGGGAAGUGAGGGCUUGAGACGGGGGGAGGGAUAGUGAAAAUGUACAACCAGUGGAUUAUAGGUGUGUUAAAGUAGGGGAACUAGAAAGAAUGACCUGGAAAUGUAAGAAGUGGGCCGGGCGCAGUGGCUCAUGCCUGUAAUCCCAGCACUUUAGGAGGCUGAGGUGGGUGGAUCAUGAGGUCCAGAGAUCAAGACCAUCCUGGCCAAUAUGGUGCAACCCCAUCUCUACUAAAAAUACAAAAAUUAGCUGGGCGUGGUGGUGUGCCUGUAGUCCCAGCUACUAGGGAGGCUGAGGCAGGAGAAUCGCUUGAACCCAGGAUGCGAAGGUUGCAGUGAGCCGAGAUUGUGCCACUGCACUCCAGGCUGGCGACAGAGCGAGACUCUGUCCCAAAAAAAAAAAAAAGUGGUGGGCUGGCCACGAUGGCUCACGCCUAUAAUCCCAGCACUUUGGGAGGCCACGGCAAGUGGAUCAUUUAAGGUCAGGAGUUCAAGACCAGUCUGGCUAAUAUGAUGAAACCCCUUCUGUAUUAAAAAUACAAAUAUUAGCCGGGCAUGGUGGCACAUGCCUGUAGUCCCAGCUACUCAGGAGGCUGAGGCAGGAGAAUCUUUGAACCCAGGAAGUGACAGUUACAACGAGCGGAGACUGUGCCACUUCACUGCAGCCUGGGUGACAGGGUGAGAGUCUGUCUCAAAAAAAGAAAAAGGAAAUGUAAGAAGUGGUGAUUGGAGAAUGGUGUGCUUAAUUAAAAUUGAGGUUUUGAGGAGUUACUAGUAAUGACAAAUAUGACCAACGGAGUGACUGGCUGAGGGGAGAGAGGAGAGGACUUAAGCAACUGUGCCACUCAGCAUUGGAAAGGUCACCUCUGUGACAUUAAAAUCAAGAAUUCUGAUAGAAGUAAGAGUUCUGGCAUGAGUGGUGCUUUUCCAGAGUACACUUGGAUAUAUGAUUACAUUUUAAUAAGUUAUAUAAAUAUGCAGAUAUUCAUGCGGCUUUUCCUCAUUUGGGAUUUUGGAAACUAAAAUAGUAGUAAGAGCAUUAAAAAAAAGAUGUCCUGGAA